GGCGCAGAGCGGUUUGGUCGUUCGUUGGACCAGUGUCGGUUCUUCGCUCGCGACUGCGGCUCUUCCUCGGGCAGCGGAAGCAGCGCGGAGGUCGGAGAAGUGGCCUAAAACUUCGGCGUUGGGUGAAAGAAAAUGGCCCGAACCAAGCAGACUGCUCGUAAAUCCACCGGUGGGAAAGCCCCCCGCAAACAGCUGGCCACGAAAGCUGCCAGGAAAAGCACCCCCUCUACCUGCGGGGUGAAGCCUCAUCGCUACAGGCCUGGGACCGUGGCGCUUCGAGAGAUUCGUCGUUAUCAGAAGUCGACCGAGCUGCUCAUCCGGAAGCUGCCCUUCCAGAGGUUGGUGAGGGAGAUCGCGCAGGAUUUCAACACUGACCUGAGGUUUCAGAGCGCAGCCGUCGGUGCGCUGCAGGAGGCUAGCGAAGCGUACCUGGUGGGUCUGUUGGAAGAUACUAACCUGUGUGCCAUCCACGCUAAGAGAGUCACCAUCAUGCCCAAAGACAUCCAGUUGGCUCGCCGGAUACGGGGAGAGAGAGCUUAAGUGAAGGCAGUUUUUAUGGCAUUUUGUAGUAAAUUCUGUAAAAUACUUUGGUUUAAUUGGUGACUUUUUUUGUAAGAAAUUGUUUAUAUGUUGCAUUUGUACUUAAGUCAUUCCAUCUUUCACUCAGGAUGAAUGCGAAAAGUGACUGUUUACAGACCUCAGUGAUGUCAGCACUGUUGCUCAGGAGUGACAAGUUGUUAAUAUGCAAAACGGAUGCGUGAUAUUUCUUGCUUCUCAUGAUGCAUGUUUCUGUAUGUUAAUGACUUGUUGGGUAGCUAUUAAGGUACUAGAAUUGAUAAAUGUGUACAACAGGGUCCUUUUGCAAUAAAACUGGUUAUGACUUGAUCCAAGUGUUUAACAAUUGGGGCUGUUAAGUCUGACCAUACAUCACUGUGAUAGAAUGUAGGCUUUUUCAAGGGUGAAGAUACAAACCUUAACCACAGUGUAACUUAUAGUUUCCUUUAAAAAAAAAAAAUUAAACCUGGCAGCUAUAGAAUACAAUAUGUGCAUUUAUAAUAGCUAUUUUAUAUAUUGUAGUGUCAACAUUUUCAAAUUAAAUGUUUUACAUUCACAA